AGCCGUCCGCGGAGCCGAGCCGGGUAGCCCCUCUCACACGGCCGUGGCCGCAACCUCAGCCCUCCUCGCACCUCCCUUCGCAGCUCACGCCCCCUCCCGUGGGGUGUCCUGGCCUCCGCCUGCCGAGCUCGGCAGUCAGCAGAGCCCCGGCCAUCCUCCUCCGGCCGUCCGGUCCCCACUGGUCCCUGGCUAGCCACUUUUCGUAAGCUAGAGCACUCCAGACCGCCCCGCCUGCGAUCAGGCGCUGCGGAAGACAGCCCUGUGGGCUGGAGCGACGACAAGGACCUCGCGGAGCGGCGAAAGGGGUGUAGUCUGCGACUACCGCGGCAGGGAGCCGGGAGGGCGGCCAAAAGUGACUUCGAAUUGCAGCUAGCCGUUUGGAACGUGGCCCAAGAGGCUCUCAUUUUCCUGGCUGGAACCGUCGCCGCGGUGCUUGCCUGCGGUCCUGGUCAGCCGUUGCCCUCCCGCCGGGCGGGCGAAGACUGGUGCAUGCUGGGAUUUGUAGUUCGUCCCCAUGAGGCUCGUCCUGGGAACAUUAUGGGGAGGAACGGAGCCUAAUCCUGUCAGCGCAGCCUGGGGAUUAGGACCCGGAGUUGCCAAGAGAGAAGAAGAAGGAGGUUCCUGCUGUGCCAGAAACCCUUAAGAAAAAGCGAAGGAAUUUCGCAGAGCUGAAGAUCAAGCGCCUGAGAAAGAAGUUUGCCCAAAAGAUGCUUCGAAAGGCAAGGAGGAAGCUUAUCUAUGAAAAAGCAAAGCACUAUCACAAGGAAUAUAGGCAGAUGUACAGAACUGAAAUUCGAAUGGCGAGGAUGGCAAGAAAAGCUGGCAACUUCUAUGUACCUGCAGAACCCAAAUUGGCGUUUGUCAUCAGAAUCAGAGGUAUCAAUGGAGUGAGCCCAAAGGUUCGAAAGGUGUUGCAGCUUCUUCGCCUUCGUCAAAUCUUCAAUGGAACCUUUGUGAAGCUCAACAAGGCUUCGAUUAACAUGCUGAGGAUUGUAGAGCCAUAUAUUGCAUGGGGGUACCCCAAUCUGAAGUCAGUAAAUGAACUAAUCUACAAGCGUGGUUAUGGCAAAAUCAAUAAGAAGCGAAUUGCUUUGACAGAUAACGCUUUGAUUGCUCGAUCUCUUGGUAAAUACGGCAUCAUCUGCAUGGAGGAUUUGAUUCAUGAGAUCUAUACUGUUGGAAAACGCUUCAAAGAGGCAAAUAACUUCCUGUGGCCCUUCAAAUUGUCUUCUCCACGAGGUGGAAUGAAGAAAAAGACCACCCAUUUUGUAGAAGGUGGAGAUGCUGGCAACAGGGAGGACCAGAUCAACAGGCUUAUUAGAAGAAUGAACUAAGGUGUCUACCAUGAUUAUUUUUCUAAGCUGGUUGGUUAAUAAACAGUACCUGCUCUCAAAUUGAAAUAUAUUGUUGUAUUUGUGAUUUGUUGUUGUUGUUGUUAGCCUGCCUCUGUCUUCCCUUAACUACUGUGGCAAGUGUGGUGUGUGAUAAAAUUAAGCCAAAUCAACAGCCCAUUUCGUGCAAAAUCAGGGUCGAGUCUGUGUGAAAGACAUCUCUUGGGUUUUUAAAAGGCUUUUCUAUACAAAAGAUUUUAAUUUUUUGUUUUUUAACUGUGCUGAGUGAUUCGAAAUGGGUUUAUUCUAAGAAAGCCUGUUUCACAAGCAUUUGUACAUGAUUUGUCGGUAAGGUAAUCCAACUUUGGUUUAUGGAAAAAAUUGAAUUUAGUUGCUAAAAUUUAUUUCUCGGGCCUUCGCUUGUUUAUAAACUGCCAUGUAAAUGUGUUGUUUUCCUUUUGCAUUCCA